GAUUCCCGGGACUAGGUUGCGGGAGAAAGCCUGUUGCGUGGAAGAUAAGGCGGCGCGGGAAGUGGACACAGGGUGGGCUGGAGGUGUGCUUCGCGUGUGAUGCCAGGGGAGUGGAAAGGUGGCUUGGGGAGUGCAGAACCCUGAGGAUAGUGGCGGGGAGGAAGAUGGGGCGUGCAGGCCGCCCCCAGUGAGGAGAGGCCAGGAUGCAGGGCGGCUCCAGGGCAAUCUGGGCAGUUGGGGGAGCCCUCCGUAUCGUUCCCGGAGGUAGCAGGAGUAGCUGUGCGGGAGGUGCCACUCCUGGGCGCUUGCUUUGCCUCCAGCAUGACCCCCGACCCUGGCUUGCACCCUGAAUCUAGCUGCGAGCCUUGGGCAGAAUGGAUACCUGAGGAAAGGUAUGGUUUCUCUCCAGCUCAGAUCUAACUGGACUCUCGCUCCUGCUGGCUGGACAUGGAGGAUUUGGAGGAAGAUGUAAGGUUUAUUGUGGAUGAGACCUUGGACUUUGGGGGGCUGUCACCAUCUGACAGCCGUGAGGAGGAAGACAUAACAGUGUUGGUGACUCCAGAGAAACCACUUCGACGGGGCCUCUCCCACCGAAGUGACCCAAAUGCAGUGGCACCUGCCCCCCAGGGUGUGAGGCUCAGCCUAGGCCCCCUCAGUCCAGAGAAGCUGGAGGAGAUCCUCGAUGAGGCCAACCGGCUGGCCGCUCAGCUGGAGCAGUGUGCCCUGCAGGAUCGGGAGAGCGCAGGCGAGGGCCUGGGGCCUCGCCGAGUGAAGCCCAGUCCUCGGCGGGAGACCUUUGUGCUGAAGGAUAGUCCUGUCCGAGACCUGCUGCCCACUGUGAACUCUUUGACGCGGAGCACCCCCUCCCCAAGCAGCCUGACGCCUCGACUCCGGAGUAAUGAUAGGAAGGGGUCAGUCAGGGCUCUCCGGGCUACAUCUGGAAAGAGGCCCUCCAACAUGAAGAGGGAGUCACCCACUUGCAAUCUGUUCCCUGCAUCCAAAAGCCCAGCAUCUUCUCCUCUUACCCGAUCGACUCCCCCAGUCCGGGGGAGAGCCGGGCCCAGUGGGAGAGCAGCAGCCAGUGAGGAGACCAGAGCAGCCAAGUUGCGGGGAGCAGCUGCUAAAUCUUCCAGUCAACUGCCCAUUCCCUCGGCCAUCCCCAGGCCUGCCAGCCGAAUGCCACUCACCAGCCGGAGUGUGCCACCUGGCAGAGGUGCCCUACCUCCGGAUUCUCUGUCAACUCGAAAAGGGCUUCCAAGACCAAGCACUGCAGGACACAGAGUGCGGGAAAGUGGACACAAGGUUCCUGUUUCCCAGCGACUAAAUCUUCCUGUCAUGGGUGCCACUCGCAGCAAUCUGCAGCCCCCCAGGAAAGUGGCAGUCCCAGGACCUACCAGGUAAAGAGAUCAGGACAGCAAGCAAGACUUCAGUAGCAAACCACUACAGUCAGUACCUGGACUCGCCUCUACCCAGCAGACCCUGACUCCAGCAGAUUCUGGCCCAGGGACAGGAGGAAGAGAUGCCACCAGGGCUGGUCUCCCAGGAGUAGAGACCAUGGGAAAUGGGGUGGAUUAGGAUUGAGCUGGAGAAGACUUAAACUCUCUGGGUUGAAAGAAGAUUAGGGGAAAAGAGGUCACCUUCCAGCAGUGAAAUGAACAAAUAGAAGAUGAGAAGUACAGGCAAGUGGUUUGUCUUUAUCCACCCCCACUGUUGUGGUCAGCCCCAGAGAAUUUUAUCUUCUUCCUUGGCAUUGGUUCACUGGACAUUUCCACGUGAGCGGCCUCCGUAGCUAACCUCCCUGCCCUCUGAGGAGCCAUCUUCCUGAAUCGCAUUCUCUACUGGACUCUGGCCUGCUUGGAGAGGUGGCAGCAGGCACCUGGUCUUCAGAAAUUGUUUCCUGUGAAUUCUGUGACUCCUAAUAGGCCAGUUUGUGAUAAGCUUACUCUAUGAGUCUUCAUUUUUCUAAAAUAAAGUGAAUGUAUUUUUAUAUUCUCUGUA